AAACUAUCGUCCAGACCCUGAAUCCUCCGGCUGUACUGCCAAGUCAUUUCCUAGGGCCGCACUCAAGGUGUCAGACUCACGUGGGCUCAUCACUGCGUCCUCUCAUAUUUUCAAUAUGAAUGACUUUUAUCAGGAAAUCUGAAAAUUAGUGAAAGGUUCAUUUUUCUCAGCAUCCGGAAGGCUCGAAGGGCAGGCAGGAGGGGCGCGAACAGGGGCUUUGCCCUCCUGGAGAGACAGCAUGAACACAGAUGUUCCCAGCGCAGGCGAAGGAGAAUGCUGGCUUCAGCGGUUGUGGGGGAGACACAGAGAUUGACUGGAAGGCCUACAUGGCCGAGGUAGAAGGCGUCAUCAAUGGUACCUAUGACUAUACCCAACUGCAGGGUGACACCGGACCACUUGUGUACCCAGCUGGUUUCGUGUACAUCUUUAUGGGGUUGUACUAUGCCACCAGCCGAGGCACUGACAUCCGCAUGGCCCAGAACAUCUUUGCUGUGCUCUACCUGGCUACCUUGCUGCUUGUCUUCUUGAUCUAUCACCAGACCUGCAAGGUACCUCCCUUCGUCUUUUUCUUCAUGUGCUGCGCCUCUUACCGUGUCCACUCCAUCUUUGUGCUGCGGCUCUUCAAUGACCCAGUGGCCAUGGUGCUGCUCUUCCUCAGUAUCAACCUCCUGCUGGCCCAGCGCUGGGGCUGGGGUUGCUGCUUUUUCAGCCUGGCAGUCUCUGUGAAGAUGAAUGUGCUGCUCUUCGCCCCUGGGUUACUGUUUCUUCUCCUCACACAGUUUGGCUUCCGUGGGGCCCUCCCCAAGCUGGGAAUCUGUGCUGGCCUUCAGGUGGUGCUGGGGCUGCCCUUCCUGCUGGAGAACCCCAGCGGCUACCUGUCCCGCUCCUUUGACCUUGGCCGCCAGUUUCUGUUCCACUGGACAGUGAACUGGCGCUUCCUCCCAGAGGCGCUCUUCCUGCAUCGAGCCUUCCACCUGGCCCUGUUGACUGCCCACCUCACCCUGCUCCUGCUGUUUGCCCUCUGCAGGUGGCACAGGACAGGGGAAAGUAUCUUGUCGCUGCUGAGGGAUCCCUCCAAAAGGAAGGUUCCACCCCAGCCCCUUACACCCAACCAGAUCGUUUCUACCCUCUUCACCUCCAACUUCAUUGGCAUCUGCUUCAGCCGCUCCCUCCACUACCAGUUCUACGUCUGGUAUUUCCACACACUGCCCUACCUCCUGUGGGCCAUGCCUGCACGCUGGCUCACACACCUGCUCAGGUUGUUGGUGCUGGGGCUCAUCGAGCUCUCCUGGAACACAUACCCUUCCACAUCCUGCAGCUCUGCUGCCCUGCACAUAUGCCAUGCCGUCAUCCUGCUGCAGCUCUGGCUGGGCCCGCAGCCUUUCCCCAAGAGCACCCAACACAGCAAGAAAGCCCACUGAAGUCCACCCCUUUCCCUCAGGACCUGAGUCUACCCUCAGGACCUGGGGUUGGUUGGACUCUGCCCUUCCAAAUAAACCUUGCUAAGUCCAACUCUGUGCAACCUACAUGGAGGUGGGGGCAGCCGAUGCCUGGUCCAGGCUGUGAGGGACACGUAUGGAGCAGAUAAAGAAUUCACUCAAGCAGU